GUACAUCCGGCGAGUAGCUGGCGGUCCCGGGUGCUGCUGGUUAGUGUGCUCUGAGGGAGGGUCCGAGCCAGCCGCUGUUUUGCCGGAGGAGCCCCUCAGGCCGGCUGCUUCCAACCUUCAAUUUGUAAAAAAACCAGAAAACCUCAGGAUCCACAAAGUAUCAUCAAAUGAGGUAGUAAGCAUUAAUAAUGUCUUUCAUCUUUGAGUGGAUCUACAAUGGCUUCAGCAGUGUGCUCCAGUUCCUAGGACUGUACAAGAAAUCUGGAAAACUUGUAUUCUUAGGUUUGGAUAAUGCAGGCAAAACCACUCUUCUUCACAUGCUCAAAGAUGACAGAUUGGGCCAACAUGUUCCAACACUACAUCCGACAUCAGAAGAGCUAACAAUUGCUGGAAUGACCUUUACAACUUUUGAUCUUGGUGGGCACGAGCAAGCACGUCGCGUUUGGAAAAAUUAUCUCCCAGCAAUUAAUGGGAUUGUCUUUCUGGUGGACUGUGCAGAUCAUUCUCGCCUCGUGGAAUCCAAAGUUGAGCUUAAUGCUUUAAUGACUGAUGAAACAAUAUCCAAUGUGCCAAUCCUUAUCUUGGGUAACAAAAUUGACAGAACAGAUGCAAUCAGUGAAGAAAAACUCCGUGAGAUAUUUGGGCUUUAUGGACAGACCACAGGAAAGGGGAAUGUGACCCUGAAGGAGCUGAAUGCUCGCCCCAUGGAAGUGUUCAUGUGCAGUGUGCUCAAGAGGCAAGGUUACGGCGAGGGUUUCCGCUGGCUCUCCCAGUAUAUUGACUGAUGUUUGGACGGUGAAAAUAAAAGAGUUUUACUUCUCUGGACUGAUCCUAUUCACAGCUUCCUCAUGAACUUUUCUAAUAGAACAAGGAAAGCUCUCCAACCAUGUCUGGCGUUGAGAAGCCAAGAGUCUCUGUCAACUCUCUCAUUGCCCAGUGGUGACAUGUGCUCUUCUCCACACUGUUGGGAGGUAAUGCUGCCCCACGUGCUGGUGCAGGUCAGUAUCCUGGGACUUGGAAGCUGGCAGGAUUUGCCGGGUAAAGCUGUAUGCCAUCAUGGGGCACCUGAAAAGAAAAACACGUCUCACCACUGUGGUUGAUUCAAAAGAAAGUGAUUCUAUUUUUUAAAGAAAGCGUUGUUAAUGUAAUUGGUAUCCCUCCUAACUUUUUGAGUUCACAAUUUACUUGGUCCAGAGUUUUCUAUUCUUUUUUUUUUUUAAACUAAUGAAUGACAUUUAGAUACUUCAUAAAAUUAUGAACAGAUAUGGAGGCCAGAGCUCAUUUGGGUAAACUUACUCCUGCUGAGUUAGCAGGUUGGUGAGAGAAGCUCCCCUGAGCUCACCUGUCUCUCUGACUGCCUUGGAGUAGGUGGCAUAACCUUGUGCACAGAGAACUAGAAAAGGGGCAGAACCCCGGCCUUGCAGUUGUGGCAGGUUUCCACUGUGGUAAGCUAGGUUCAUUCCUCAUCAAGGAAUGUGUAGCAGAUUGUUCACUGUGGAGGAGUUAAUUAUAGAAUGGGUUAUUGUUGUUAUUCUUACUCAUGAAGUUACAGAUUUUAGCCAGUCUUUGCUUUUAUACUUUUGUGAAAUUUAAUUUCUCUCUAUAGCACCUUCCUUUUUCGUUUUCAGUUAUCAAAAGUGACUUUGACCUCAUAAAAGAGUUGAGAACAUCUCUCGUGUCACAUACUGCAGGUGCAUCAGUUACUUUUGCACAGAUUCUAGGGGGACAUUUUUCUGAAUAGGAAGACAGGACAAAGUUAACAGCUUAAGGGCUCUUAAUUCUGUGAGUUGAGGACUUAAAAGUAUUGUAGCAUUUGUUUGGAUCCAUGAAAAAUGUAUUCAGUGGGCUUUAAAAUUUCCAUUUGCAGAAUUUGGUCUCUCAGGCUGUUUGGGAGCUCUUUUUUUUACAUUUUUUCUCCUUUGACACCUAUUUUAUUGGUGUUUAAAGUAAAGGUUAACAUCUGUAGCUUUUCCAGGUUUUUUUUUUUUUUUUUUUUUUUUUGGUAUGAAAUUGUCUUUCUCCAUUGCAGAAAUAAGCUAGGGAAACACUAACCCAAAAACUUUCUGUAGAGCUGUUCCUUUGGAGGCAGCAUCACUUAUUGGCAGUAAAGACUCAGUAUAAAAGCACCGGCAUCCCUACUUGGGUGAUGGGGAUUAAUUUUAUAGCAUUCCAUUUUCCUAGUGCCACAUGUGAAAUUGGAUUUUGAUGAUCUUAAUCUAUAUUCUACCCUUAUAAUAAAAGAUCAAAAGAUAUAUCUCCUAUGAACAGAUUGGAGAUAGGAGAUGAAAAGUUGGGAGGAUGUCUUUAUUCUAAUGUGAGGGUAGGGAAAAUGUGGAUAACAUUACUGGGGUGAGGGAGGCAUUGUUCUUUAGUUGGAGUUCUCAUUCUUAUUCUCCAGUACUGACUUGUGGGGAAAGCAUACUUUUUCACUGCCAGGUACUGAAUGCAGAGGCUCAGUGAAGUAUAUAUGUGGGAAGUGCAUGCAUUUCGUUUAUUAGCAAACAUAGCUGGAUUAAGACAAAGUUGUUGGUUUGGAAAGGGGUUAAAGCCUUAAGUGAACAAAUCUAGCUAACAGUGAAUGAACUAGGUAAUAUAACUUGCAUAUUUUUAAUUUCCUUUGGUUAAAGGUCCCCCAUACUUCUCUGUUCGGAGACAUGAGAAGUAUGAUUACUUCAGUGUUAGUUUUCUUAAUUUUUUUUUUCCCCUAUUUGUCCCUUGUCACUUUGUUGCAAGCUAGAAAUCUGUGGGUUAUACAUAGGGCAGCUCUUUGUGAAAGUGGUUUAUUCCACUGGAGAAAGGGGAUUGAAAAUCAGUUAGAACCAAUGUAUUUCUUGCCCCACGGAACACUAUUCCUAUAAGAUAGCUGAAAGAAGCUGCUGUGAGGAGCUCAGCUCCAAACACAGGAUCAGCACCUUGUAUAGGAAUUCCCAUGAAUUAUGACUUCUCAUUCUGUUUUAUCAGAGUGCAUAUAUGUCCUACUUCAGGAAAAGUAAAACAGUCAUUUACGAAAGAAAGUCAAUCUGUAUCCUAAGCAUUUUAAUAAAAAGUUAAAACAAAUACGCUAUUUCCUUUUUUUUUUUUCAUUGGUUUGUUCUGAGCUCUGAGUUUGAACAAUGCCGUUUAUUUGGGGAGGCAACCAAAAGUUCCCUGCAUAGAGGAAGAGACAUUUAGGGUGCGUGUGAGAUACUUGAAUUUUGCCACCAGGAGGGGGAAAAAGGCUGGGGUACUAGAAGUAAUAGAUUUAGUACUACUUGAGAGAUUUGGAACAUGCUGUGGACCCAGGGUUGUUGGUCAUCUCUGCAACAGGAUGGGGAUGGCAGAUGUUUGAGCAAAAUCUAUAUUAACAUGCUAGCAAGGACUAGUUCUAGUUUAGCUGUGUUUCACUCAUUUUACACAGAAUUAGAAUUGGCCAGGUGUGGUGGCUCACGCUGUAAUCCUAGCACUUUGGGAGGCUGAGGUGGGUGGAUUGUCUGAGCUCAGGAGUUUGAGACCAGCCUGGGGAACAGGGUGAAACCCCAUCACUACUAAAAUACAAAAAAAUUAGCUGGGCAUUGUGGUACAUGGAGUAGCUCCCAGCUACUCUGGAGGCUGAGGCGGAGAAUCGCUUGAACUAGGAGGUGGAGAUUGAAGUGAGCCGAGAUCAUGCCACUGUACUCCUGCCUGGGUGACAGAGCAAGACUCUCUCUAGCUCAAAAAAAAAAAAAAAAAAAAAAUCAAUUAAAUGCUACAUUUGGCAAAAUGAGAAAGAAAGAAUUUCCUUUACUAGGCUUGUAGGAAGACUGCUUUUACAAAAACCCAAAUGAGAUCAUAAAACUAAAGUACUGGGACAAACAGUGGGAAACAGUGCAAUGGGUUCUUUUCAACCAAGUAUUAAAGUAUUGGAGAUAUUGCCGGGCGCGGUGGCUCACGUCUGUAAUCCUAGCGCUUUGGGAGGCCAAGGCGGGCGGGUCAUGAGGUCAGGAGUUCAAGGCCAGCCUGACCAACAUGGCAGAGCUCCGUCUCUACUAAAAAUACAAAAAUUAGCCAGGCACGGUGGGACGCACCUUUAAUCCCAGCUACUCAGGAGGCUGAAGCAGGAGAAUCGCUUGAAUCGGGGAAGCGGAGGUUGCAGUGAGCCGAGAUCGCGCCACUGCACUCCAGCCUGGGUGACUCCCAUCUCAAAAAAAAUAAAAAGUACUGGAGGUGUCCUGUUGUCCUUGUUACUGUGAAAGGAUGCCAUGGGUUGUAUGGGCAAAUGAGUUGUUUUGUUUGAGGCAGAGUGGAAAAUAAGAUUAGGCUCAGUCCAUGAGCCUAGCACUCAACAGAUCUUACUUUGGCGUUCUGGCUGUGACUUGGGACUUCUUUUUACCAUGGUCUGCUGUAAACACAGAAAAACCCAAUGCCUAACAGUUCAUGCUGGAGUCUUGAGCGUUGAGGGAGAAUCACUGGACUCGAGAGAGAAAGUUUGUUUGUUUGUUUGUUUGUUUGUUUUUUGAGUUGGUCUCACUCUGUCGCCCAGGCUGGAGUGCAGUGGUAUGAACAUAGGUCACUGCAGCCUUGACCUCCUGGGCUUAAGUGAUCCUCCCAUCUCAGCCUCCCAAGUAGCUUGGGACCACAGGGUUGCACCACCGUGCUCAGCUAGUUUUCAAAAUUUUUGUAGAGUUAAGGUCUCAUCAUGUUGCCCAGGCUGGUCUCAAACUCCUGGGCUCAGGAAAUUCUCCUACCUCAGCCUCCCAACGUGCUGGGAUUCCAAGUGUGAGCCCCUGUGCUCCACCAAGAGAAAAACUCUUUGAUUGCUAGGAAGUUGGGAUAAAGAAAUUGUGCUGUGAUCAAGCCACCUUCUGUGUCAUAGAACCAAAAGAAGACCGCCUGCUAUGGCAAGAUGGCCUAAUUUUAUUCCUGCCUCAUACUAUCAUGGAUAAUCGUUUUCCUUUCUCUAGCAGGUUUGUGUCACUGGGAGUACUGGGAGCAUUAUCCUGUGUUGUGCUGGGGUUAUACCAAGCAGUGUUAACUUUAUUUAAAGAAUUCAGGCAGAAAGAUUAGAGAAUUUAAGUAGCAAUUGUAUAUGGUAAGCAAUACAGUAACCUUAAUAAAAAUUAAUGAUGGCCGGGUACGGUGGCUCACGCCUGUAAUCCCAGCACUUUGGGAGGCCGAGGCGGGCGGAUCACAAGGUCAGGAGAUCGAGACCAUCCUGGCUAACACGGUGAAACCCCGUCUCUACUAAAAAUACAAAAAAUUAGCUGGGCGUGGUGGCAGGCGCCUGUAGUCCCAGCGACUGGGGAGGCUGAGGCAGGAGAAUAGCGUGAACCCAGGAGGCGGAGUUUGCAGUGAGCGGAGAUCGCACCAUUGCACUCCAGCCUGGGCGACAGAGCGAGACUCCGUCUCAAAAAAAUAAAUAAAUAAAUAAAAAAUAAUGUGUAUUUUAUCAAUUCAGUGAUAAAGCAGACCUUUGUAAACUGUCUAGCUUGUGGUGACUGAUUGAGGGUAUCAUGAAGCUCCGCGCCCCCCCACUCCCCGACAUACUCGUUCAUCCUCCUCUGUCCUAAAGCGUACUUCUUUGGAAAAGUAGAGCAGUUUAUGUUAGUGUACACUAGAGAUGGUAAACUAUGCCUUGUGGGUCAAAUCGGGCCUGCUGCCUGUGUUUGUAUGGCCUGUGAGCAAAGAAAGGUUUUUACAUAUUUAAAUGGUUGGAAAAAAUAUUUAAAGAAUGCUAUUUUUGGACACAAAAAAUUGUAUGAAAUUAAAAUUUCAAUGUCUGUAUCUUUUUAUUGGGACACAGCCACCGCCAUUCCUUUAGCUUUUGUAUGCAACAGCUGCAGAGUUGACUAUUUGAGACAAGUUGUAUGGUCCCCCCAAACUGGAACUGUUUCCAUUCUGGCCUUCUACAGAAAGUAUUUGGACCCUGGCCUAGAUAAAUCCUGGCUGGUGGUUAUGUUAUGUGAAAUGUGCACACUGUAAAAUAUAGGCCUGUAUGAUUAAAAUUUUUGAUUUCA